AGCCUCGCUUCGCCAGGGUCGCUGGCGGACGCGCGCCGCAGUCCGAGCCUCAGACGCGCGGGCGCGGGGGACGGCGCAGGGGCCGCCUGGCUGGAGCAGCCAGAGGGGAUAGCUUCGUCGAGAACGGAGGACACCGGCGGUCCAGGGUCCUGGGCAGUCGCGCCAGAGCUGAGCGGAGGGCGCGGCGCGAGAACGAAUCUUUGUGACAUUCUCUCUCAGCAUUCUUUAUCCCCUGUUUGCUGAAGACUUCGACAAAAGCUGGUCUUAGCUGUUGGCAUUCUCCUGAGAAAAGGAUAGCUUCAGAAAUCAGAAAAACAUUUGGGAGGUGUCUAGCCCAGUGGACCUUCUGAAGAGCAAUGCUAAGAAGACGUUUGGUUUAAAGAAUUAAAAGGAAGAACAACUUAAGAGCUUCUUCAAAGGUGGACUGGCCUCCUUGAUGCCCCAUGAGCAAGCCAGGAUGCUCCCACCACAGGGUCUUUCACCGAGGCUCCCUCUGUCUGGAACACUCUUCCUGCACAUAUCCCCAUAGCUCGCUGCUUCUUCUUUAGGUCUUUGCUCAGAUAUCAUUUUCUGUUUCCCGCAUGAAAAUUACUUAAACGUUGCACACAACGUUUCACAAAAUCUUUUGUGAAAGAAGAAAAGGAAAUUCAGUGUGUGAGUCUCAGCAGGAGUUAAGCUAAUGCAGCUUAAAAUAAUGCCGAAAAAGAAGCGCUUAUCUGCGGGCAGAGUGCCCCUGAUUCUCUUCCUGUGCCAGAUGAUUAGUGCACUGGAAGUACCUCUUGAUCCAAAACUUCUUGAAGACUUGGUACAGCCUCCAACCAUCACCCAACAGUCUCCAAAAGAUUACAUUAUUGACCCUCGGGAGAAUAUUGUAAUCCAGUGUGAAGCCAAAGGGAAACCGCCCCCAAGCUUUUCCUGGACCCGUAAUGGGACUCAUUUUGACAUCGAUAAAGACCCUCUGGUCACCAUGAAGCCUGGCACAGGAACGCUCAUAAUUAACAUCAUGAGCGAAGGGAAAGCUGAGACCUAUGAAGGAGUCUAUCAGUGUACAGCAAGGAACGAACGCGGAGCUGCAGUUUCUAAUAACAUUGUUGUCCGCCCAUCCAGAUCACCAUUGUGGACCAAAGAAAAACUUGAACCAAUCACACUUCAAAGUGGUCAGUCUUUAGUACUUCCCUGCAGACCCCCAAUUGGAUUACCACCACCUAUAAUAUUUUGGAUGGAUAAUUCCUUUCAAAGACUUCCACAAAGUGAGAGAGUUUCUCAAGGUUUGAAUGGGGACCUUUAUUUUUCCAAUGUCCUCCCAGAGGACACCCGCGAAGACUAUAUCUGUUAUGCUAGAUUUAAUCAUACUCAAACCAUACAGCAGAAGCAACCUAUUUCUGUGAAGGUGAUUUCAGCUAAAUCAAGUAGAGAGAGGCCACCAACAUUUUUAACUCCAGAAGGCAAUGCAAGUAACAAAGAGGAAUUAAGAGGAAAUGUGCUUUCACUGGAGUGCAUUGCAGAAGGACUGCCUACCCCAAUUAUUUACUGGGCAAAGGAAGAUGGAAUGCUACCCAAAAACAGGACAGUUUAUAAGAACUUUGAGAAAACCUUGCAGAUCAUUCAUGUUUCAGAAGCAGACUCUGGAAAUUACCAAUGUAUAGCAAAAAACGCAUUAGGAGCCAUCCACCAUACCAUUUCUGUUAGAGUUAAAGCGGCUCCAUACUGGAUCACAGCCCCUCAAAAUCUUGUGCUGUCCCCAGGAGAGGAUGGGACCUUGAUCUGCAGAGCUAAUGGCAACCCCAAACCCAGAAUUAGCUGGUUAACAAAUGGAGUCCCAAUAGAAAUUGCCCCUGAUGACCCCAGCAGAAAAAUAGAUGGCGAUACCAUUAUUUUUUCAAAUGUUCAAGAAAGAUCAAGUGCAGUCUAUCAGUGCAAUGCCUCUAAUGAAUAUGGAUAUUUACUGGCAAACGCAUUUGUAAAUGUGCUGGCUGAGCCACCACGAAUCCUCACACCUGCAAACACACUCUACCAGGUCAUUGCAAACAGGCCUGCUUUACUAGACUGUGCCUUCUUUGGGUCUCCUCUCCCAACCAUCGAGUGGUUUAAAGGAGCUAAAGGAAGUGCUCUUCAUGAAGAUAUUUAUGUUUUACAUGAAAAUGGAACUUUGGAAAUUCCUGUGGCCCAAAAGGACAGUACAGGAACUUAUACGUGUGUUGCAAGGAAUAAAUUAGGGAUGGCGAAGAAUGAAGUUCACUUAGAAAUCAAAGAUCCUACAUGGAUCGUUAAACAGCCCGAAUAUGCAGUUGUGCAAAGAGGGAGCAUGGUGUCCUUUGAAUGCAAAGUGAAACAUGAUCACACCUUAUCCCUCACUGUCCUGUGGCUGAAGGACAACAGGGAACUGCCCAGUGAUGAAAGGUUCACUGUUGACAAGGAUCAUCUAGUGGUAGCUGAUGUCAGUGACGAUGACAGCGGGACCUACACGUGUGUGGCCAACACCACUCUGGACAGCGUCUCCGCCAGCGCUGUGCUUAGCGUUGUUGCUCCUACUCCAACUCCAGCUCCCGUUUACGAUGUCCCAAAUCCUCCCUUUGACUUAGAACUGACAGAUCAACUUGACAAAAGUGUUCAGCUGUCAUGGACCCCAGGCGAUGACAACAAUAGCCCCAUUACAAAAUUCAUCAUCGAAUAUGAAGAUGCAAUGCACAAGCCAGGGCUGUGGCACCACCAAACUGAAGUUUCUGGAACACAGACCACAGCCCAGCUGAAGCUGUCUCCUUACGUGAACUACUCCUUCCGCGUGAUGGCAGUGAACAGCAUUGGGAAGAGCUUGCCCAGCGAGGCGUCUGAGCAGUAUUUGACGAAAGCCUCAGAACCAGAUAAAAACCCCACAGCUGUGGAAGGACUGGGAUCAGAGCCUGAUAAUUUGGUGAUUACGUGGAAGCCCUUGAAUGGUUUCGAAUCUAAUGGGCCAGGCCUUCAGUACAAAGUUAGCUGGCGCCAGAAAGAUGGUGAUGAUGAAUGGACAUCUGUGGUUGUGGCAAAUGUAUCCAAAUAUAUUGUCUCAGGCACGCCAACCUUUGUUCCAUACCUGAUCAAAGUUCAGGCCCUGAAUGACAUGGGGUUUGCCCCCGAGCCAGCUGUAGUCAUGGGACAUUCUGGAGAAGACCUCCCAAUGGUGGCUCCUGGGAACGUGCGUGUGAAUGUGGUGAACAGUACCUUAGCCGAGGUGCACUGGGACCCAGUACCUCUGAAAAGCAUCCGAGGACACCUACAAGGCUAUCGGAUUUACUAUUGGAAGACCCAGAGUUCAUCUAAAAGAAACAGACGUCACAUUGAGAAAAAGAUCCUCACCUUCCAAGGCAGCAAGACUCAUGGCAUGUUGCCGGGGCUAGAGCCCUUUAGCCACUACACACUGAAUGUCCGAGUGGUCAAUGGGAAAGGGGAGGGCCCAGCCAGCCCUGACAGAGUCUUUAAUACUCCAGAAGGAGUCCCCAGUGCUCCCUCGUCUUUGAAGAUUGUGAAUCCAACACUGGACUCUCUCACUUUGGAAUGGGAUCCACCGAGCCACCCGAAUGGCAUUUUGACAGAGUACACCUUAAAGUAUCAGCCAAUUAACAGCACACAUGAAUUAGGCCCUCUGGUAGAUUUGAAAAUUCCUGCCAACAAGACACGGUGGACUUUAAAAAAUUUAAAUUUCAGCACUCGAUAUAAGUUUUAUUUCUAUGCACAAACAUCAGCAGGAUCAGGAAGUCAAAUUACAGAGGAAGCAGUAACAACUGUGGAUGAAGCUGGUAUUCUUCCACCUGAUGUAGGUGCAGGCAAAGUUCAAGCAGUAAAUCCCAGGAUCAGCAAUCUUACUGCUGCAGCUGCUGAGACCUAUGCCAAUAUCAGUUGGGAAUAUGAGGGACCAGAGCAUGUGAACUUUUAUGUUGAAUAUGGUGUAGCAGGCAGCAAAGAAGAAUGGAGAAAAGAAAUUGUAAAUGGUUCUCGGAGCUUCUUUGGGUUAAAGGGUCUAAUGCCAGGAACAGCAUACAAAGUUCGAGUUGGUGCUGUGGGGGACUCUGGUUUUGUGAGUUCAGAGGAUGUGUUUGAGACAGGCCCAGCGAUGGCAAGCCGGCAGGUGGAUAUUGCAACUCAGGGCUGGUUCAUUGGUCUGAUGUGUGCUGUUGCUCUCCUUAUCUUAAUUUUGCUGAUUGUUUGCUUCAUCAGAAGAAACAAGGGUGGUAAAUAUCCAGUUAAAGAAAAGGAAGAUGCCCAUGCUGACCCUGAAAUCCAGCCUAUGAAGGAAGAUGAUGGGACAUUUGGAGAAUACAGUGAUGCAGAAGACCACAAGCCUUUGAAAAAAGGAAGUCGAACUCCUUCAGACAGGACUGUGAAAAAAGAAGAUAGUGACGACAGCCUAGUUGACUAUGGAGAAGGGGUUAAUGGCCAGUUCAAUGAGGAUGGCUCCUUUAUUGGACAAUACAGUGGUAAGAAAGAGAAAGAGCCGGCUGAAGGAAACGAAAGCUCAGAGGCACCUUCUCCUGUCAACGCCAUGAAUUCCUUUGUUUAAUUUUUAAGCUCUUUGCCAAUAUUCCAUUUCUCUAGAAUGUUUAUCCUAAGCACUUGUUUGUCAGCCCUCUCAUACUAUGAACAUAUGGGUAGAGAGUAUAUUUUCUGCUGUAUGUUAGUAUUAUGAGAAUAGUUACAGCAAAAACAUAACUCAGUCAAAUGAUAUGUUAAUAUGAACUGGAAUGCAAAGUGCAUACUUUUUCAUUCAAAAUGGGUAUUCUUGAUUUCCUCAGAACUGAUAAAAAAUAAUGCAACAUCACCAACAGAUCCUGUUAUUUCCUCUGCAGGAUACAGUUCAAUAUGAUGCAUGAAAAAUGCUCCACAUUUAAAGGACAUACCCGUGUAUGUUAUGAAAACAUGGUUUGAUACUUUGUUUAUACUACCCUCAGCUGAACCCCUAUAUAUGAAUUCCGUUUUCAUUGUCAAGAAUGUUACUGUAGUAUUCUCUAGAACUUCAAUGUCUUUGUGGACAUUGUUGUGAAAUUGGUGACUAUGUAUAGCUGUCGUUAGUCUUUUUGGGAGACUGUUAGGAACAGUUUGUACAGUAUAUACUUGCUAAAUGAGUUCAUUAUGACAGUCACAUUGCUGAUGCUUACUGAGAACUAUUACCUACUCUUGGCUCCUGUUACUCCGUAGGCUUCUUAAUCUUCCAGGCAUUACAGCAGCACAGUGUUCUACUUUUUACAUCAUUUCUAUGUUCGGUUGUUUUUAGGCAUAAACAAUGUGUAUUGCAGUGCAUUUCGGCAUUUGUGCCAUACUGAAAGAAUCAAAAACAAAUCAUCCAAAUUAAAUUUCAAACAUUAUUUCAGAGAACACAGGGCAAGACACAUACAGUGCCUUCAGAUAUUAAGCAUUCCACAACAUCGUGCAUUCUGUAUCAGCUGGUCCAGUCCAUUCUGGGUCCUAGAUUACUGUCAUUGUCUAAAAGUAACUUUUAAAAAGCAGAGUUCAUGAAAACUGCAAUGCUGGGAAAAGAAGGAAACAUGAAAAUAAAAAUAAGACAGUUUAUUAGAAAUAGCAUUUCCUCAUAAGCAUAAAAAGAAAAUCUUUGUUGCCAACUGAAGCACAUGAUGAUUUUGUGGUCCUUUAUGGUUUCUAUUACAUUCAGUAAGAAAGAUGUCAACAUGCUAGAAAAUUAAUUUUAAAACUAAGUUAUUCCAACACUAAAAGCAUACAACAGCAUGCCAACAGUAAUAUAUUAUUCUCCAAGACUUUACCUAUGUAAGUGUUCAAAACUCUGCAGCAUUAAACAACGUGUAUGCAAAUUGUUAUGGAUACAUUUCAGAAUCUAAGAAAUCAGGCAAGUGCUUAAAAGGCCAACGGUCCAAGGGAUUACAUCUGCAGUUUAAAAAGUAAAUAUAUAUUCUAUCGUAUUCAUAAACAAUAUCUAUCAAAUGGGUUACCUCCAAAUAUGAAAAUCUAUAACAACCUAUGGUUGAAGGAAUGCUCAGUUUCAUUUGCCAAUAAAUUGGUUUCUCAUAACUUGCAUCAAGUUUAAUUUUAAGUAAAGCUUUUUAUAUGUAGAUAUUUUGUUGAAUUUGUAAAUACACUUAAAAUGUAGAUGCUAUAUGCUUAUAGGUGUUACAUACAAAUAAACAUGCAAUGUUUAUGUUGUACUGUAUAAGAGGUAAGCUAAUUAAUGCAGUGAAUGGGAUUGGAAAGCAUCUACUUAAAUAUCUAUUGGGUUCCCCCCUCCCCCCACCUUUUUUGCUGUGAAACUGAAAUAGUGAACUUUUCUACGUAUUGACAGCAGAUUUUUCGAUGAAAUCUUCAGAGCUUUGCCUAUGGGGCACAGUAGGCCUAGUAACCUGGCAUGUUUGAUAUAUGUAGGUAAAGCAUAAUUUAAAGUAAUCCCAGGUAAAGAUGGCCCUAAAUACUUUCAUGUCUCUAUAUUCAUUUUUCACAGAUCCACCUGUCUCUUGAAAAUAUAAAAAGACAAAACAGGUUUGCCUUGGCAUCAGAGAGCACAAAGAUUAAAAGUUACUUUAAAUUUGCCAAUAUUUUGGGAGAACAAUAAAACUACAUUUUUUCCUCUUCCAUACUGGUAGAUGCGAAAUUUAUCUGUGCAUGAAAGGGUCACUUCUGUAAUAGUGCAACAGAUUUGGUAUUAAAAAUUAAAUGUGGUUUUAAAAGUUCCUCUCUCUUUUGUAAUUUAUGUUCCCAAUUGAGUGUGAAUGUCCAAGUAAUGGUGUAUGUAAUGGUACAGGCAAAUGUGACUGGAUUUCCCUCAAAAAAGUAACUAUUAAACAGUCUUGAUCUCUU